GCAGAUCGCUUGCAGCUUGCUAGCUGUGUGGGCUGGGAGGUCUGGUAGGGCUGAGCUUGCAAGAGGAUCAACAUGCCUUUGGCUAGAGAUUUACUACAUCCGUCCUUGGAAGAGGAAAAGAAAAAACAUAAAAAGAAACGCCUAGUACAAAGUCCAAAUUCUUACUUUAUGGAUGUAAAAUGUCCAGGUUGCUACAAGAUCACCACGGUUUUCAGCCAUGCUCAGACAGUGGUUCUUUGUGUAGGUUGUUCAACAGUGUUGUGCCAGCCUACAGGAGGAAAGGCCAGACUCACAGAAGGGUGUUCAUUUAGAAGAAAGCAACACUAAUGAUUCAAACAGCUUCCUGAAUUUUAAUUUUGUGUUGUCUCACAGAAAGCCUUAUCAUAAAUUCCAUAAUUCUAAUUAAUUUACCAAGAUAAUGUAAUUACAUUUGGUUUUGUAAGGUAUACAGCAGUAAUCUCCUAUUUUGGUGUCAGUUUUUCAAUAAAGUUUUGAUUAUGGGCAAAUCCCCUCUUUUUCUUUUUUUAAAAUAUAUUUGAGUAUGCCAUACAUUUAUAUAUAUGGUGUAUAUGAAUUUGGUUUAAACAUUUUAAAAUUUAUUCUGAUUAGUUUGUGUCUUUUUUUUUUUUUUUGAGAGAGAGAGUCCUGCUCUGUCACUCAAGCUGGAGUGCAGUGGUGCGAUCUCGGCUCACUGCAACCUCCGCCUCCCAGGUCCAAGCAAUUCUCUUGCCUUGUCCUCCCAAGUAGCUGGGAUUAUAGGCACACACCACCAUGCCUGGCUAAUUUGUGUCUCAUUUUCAAGAGUAGAAACCCUAAAUAUUUUAUUUUCAUUCCUUUUCCAAAUUGCUAUGAAUGGGAUUAAAGGAUUACAGAUGUAAAGUCUAUUAUUUGUGAAUUCUAAAUGUAGUUCUGCUGUUGUACCUGUGGAAACAUCUUAAAGAAGUACAUAUUUUGCACGUCCUGCACGUGUACCCCAGAACUUAAACUAUAAUUAAAAAGAAUAGUUUCAAAAAAAUACAUAUUGAUCACAGUGUAAUGCCUUGGAUUUAUGUGGCCUUGCUAUACUACUAUAUAAUUUAGGACAGUAACUGCUAGCUGGGGUGUGAGUUAUUUAUUGGAAGCUCCUUUUUAGGGUAGAAAAUUUGAGGAGAAAUCUGAAGUGGCAUGAUUUACCCGCAGAAGUCCUGGUUGGGGAUAGUAGAUGGUGUUGAAUUCUCUGGCCCAGAUAGGUGAGCACUCCUGACUACAGAUGUGUGUUGAGUGGUUCUGGUGCCUGCCUCAUUGUCAUUUUCAUAGUUUAUGAAGUAAUCCUGGGGAGCUGAGACGGGGAGUGUAUCCACUCACUAUACAACUCCUCAUUGGACUAGGAAGAUAGUCCAGUUUCUACUCUGCUUCUAUUUGAUUUGUUACCUUGUGGCAGGUAUUUAAAACAGGCAUUUCCUAUCAACAGGUAGGCCUCUAAUGUGAGCAACUGAUCCUCUUACAUACUGCUUAAAUCAGAGAACUGUUGCACAAGAACUAAAGAAUGAUGGCAAGUUUGGGGUGUAUAUAGUUGUAUAAGGAAGGCUGGGCGCAGUGGCUCACACCUGUAAUCCCAGCACUUUGGGAGCCUGAGGCAGGUGGAUCACCUGAGGUCGGGAGUUCAAGACCAGCCUGACCAACAUGGAAAAACCCCGUCUCUACUAAAAAUGCAAAAUUAGCUGGGCGUGGUGGUGCAUGCCUGUAAUCUCAGCUAACUCGGGAGGCUGAGGCAGGAGAAUUCGCUUGAACCUGGGAGGUGGAGGUUGUGGUGAGCCAAGAUCGUGCCAUUGCACUCUAGCCUGGGCAACAAGCACGAAACUCCGUCUCAAAAAAAAAAAGAAAAAAAAAAUAUAUAUAUAUACAUAUAUAUGUAGAUGACCCAGAGAUUCUCAGACUUUUAGUUUCUGACAUCAUUAGAAUCUCAGUAAUUUUUUUCAGGCCAUUCCUUGGCCAAAAGAAAUACCUAACAGUUACAUUUAUUAACUUAUGUUCUAACAACUCUAGUAGCCAUUUGAAAAAAACUAUACACACACAAGAGCAAAAGUGAUGUGAUGAUUUUUUUAAAAAUAGAGACAGUGUCUUGGCUCUAUUGCCCAGGUUGGAGGGUCAUAGCUCAUUGUGACCUCAAACUCCUGGGCUCAAGCAAGCCUCCCACCUCUGCCUCCUGAGUAGCGGAGACUUCAGGCACGUGCCACCACGCCCGCCUAAUUUUUUUGUAGAGAUGGGGCUCUGGCUGUGUUGCCCAGGCUGUAAGGAACUCCUGGCCUCAGGUGAUCUGCCUUGGCCUACCAAAGUGCUGGGAUUACAGGUGUGAGCCACUGUGCCCAGCCUGAUGUGAUAAUUUUUAUCUCAUCCUUAAAUCAUCACAGUUACUAAUGGAAUGUGUGUGCCUUUUGGGCUCCAUACAGUUUCUCAAAAUUGAAAUCAGAUUGGACACCAUUGUCCUUAUUUCUUCCACAUUGAUUUUUGCAUGGUGCUUUUUGUCAUAGCAGUGGCUCCAAACCCAGCUUCACAAGGAUAGGAUGCCAUCAAAGGGAAUGUAGUGCCAUAUCAUAUUGAAACUGAACUUCCUGGAACUAGUAGUUUAUACAAAAGAUGCGUCAGUGUCAAGUGUUUUUCCUGAGGUACUCCAAGGCACUUCAGCUUGCACAGUUUAGGAUACUUGGCUAUAAGGAGAGACAGUGGGAUGACAGCUUUUGAUGAGAAGGAAUCAAACCUAUGAUGAGGACUAAUCUAACAAACCCUGAAAAUUCCCUUGGAAGUAUUUUUUAAAAAAGGAUUAUACUUUAAAGACCACAUCUAAGGGCUGGGCGCGGUGGCUCACACCUAUAAUCCCAGCAGUUUGGGAGGCUGAGGCAGGCAGAUCACUUGCAGUCAGGAGUUCGAGACCAGCCUGGCCAACACAGUGAAACCCCGUCUCUACUAAACAUACAAAAAUUAGCUGGGCGUGGUGGUGUACACCUGUAGUCCCAGCUACUUGGGAGGCUGAGGCACAAGAAUUGCUUGAAACCAGGAGGCAGAGGUUGCAGUGAGCCAAAAUCGCACCACUGCACUUCAGCCUGGGUGACAGCGUGAAGCUGUGUCUCAAAGAAAGAACACAUCUAAGGAUUUACAUGGCAUUGGGAAACGAAUGGUGUAUUAAGUUUUACUUUAUUAUUAAUCUAGAUGGUAUUACUGGUUUUGAAAAGUGCUGAAUAGGACACCAGGACUUUCCCAAACUUCAGGGUCAGCCACAUACAUUAUUAUAUACUGAAUGUUUUAAAUAUUAUUUAUAUUGACUUCAUAUUUUAAUGUAAAUAUAUUUGUAAAGGAAACCUUCCAUAAACUUAAUAUAAAUUUAUUUUUAGGGGAAGGCUUCCUAAAUGGAAAAACCAGUUACAUAAAGAUAGCUAAAAAUAGGCCGGGCGCAGUGGCUCACGCCUAUAAUCCCAGCACUUUGGGAGGCCGAGGCGGGUGGAUCACGAGGUCAGGAGAUCGAGACCACCCUGGCUAACACGGUGUAACCCCGUCUCUACUAAAAAUACAAAAAAUUAGCCGGGCAUGGUGGUGGGCGCCUGUAGUCCCAGCUACUUGGGAGGCUGAGGCAGGAGAAUGGCGUGAACCUGGGAGGCGGAGCUUGCAGUGAGCCAAGAUCACGCCUCUGCACUCCAGCCUGGGUGACAGAGCAAGACUCCAGCUCAAGAAAAAAAUAAAUAAGCUAAAAAUAAAAUGAAAUUCUUGGCUUCUGGCCUGAUGAGAUGACAAAUGGUUUUGUGUCUGGUCGUUCCUGUAAGUCAUCUGAUAAAGCUCUAAUUCCUUUCUGUUUUAUUUUUCUGGAGAUAUGAUUCAGAUACUAUAAAAUCCAAACUUCUGUGAUGUAAAAGUCAGUAGUUUUUACUAUAUUUACAAGGUUGUGCAACCAUUACUACUGUCUAAUCCCAGACCAUUUUCAUCACCUUAGAAAGAAACUUCAUACCUAUCAGCAUUCACUCCCUAUUCUUCCCUCCUCUCAGCCAUUGGCAGCCACUAAGCUACUUUUGUCUCCAUGGAUUUGCUUCUUCUCAAUAUUUCAUAUAAUGCUAUUUCGUAUAAAUGGAAUCACAUGGUAUGUAGCUUCUGUAUGUUUCACUUAGCAUAAUGUUUUCAAGGGCUGUCCAUGCUGUUGCAUGUAUCAAUAUUUCAUUCCUUUUUUUGACAAUAUUCUGUGUAAUAAUAUACAAUGUUUAUCCAUUCAUCAGUUGAUAGAUACUUAGAGUGUUUUCACUUUUUAUUUAUUUAUUUUUGAGAUGGAGUCUUGCUCUGUUCCCUAGGUGGAGUGCAGUGGCGUGAUCUCAGCUCACUGCAACCUCCUCCACCUCCCAGGCUUGAGUGACCCUCUGGCCUCAGCCUCCCGAGUAGCUGGAACUACAGGCACGUGCCACCACACCCCGCUAAUUUUUUGUAUUUUUUGUAGAGAUGGGGUUUCGCCAUGUUGCCCAGGCUGGUCUUGAACUCCUUGCCUCAGGCCAUCCGCCCACCUCAGCCUCCCAAAGUGCUGGCAUUACAGGUGUGAGCCACUGCAUCCGGCCAAAUAAAGUAUUCUUAAUGACAUCUGCAAAAUCCAUUUUGCUAUGUAAGGUAACAUAUUCGUAGGUUCUGGGGAUUAGGGUGUGGGAAUCUUUAGAGGGCCAUUAUUCUGCUACCACAGAAUAUAAAGUUGUAAAAUUCUACCCCAUAUUUGGAAACUGAGAUUCUUAAAUUAUGUCUUUGUAAUUCUCUUUUUUCUUUUUCUUUCUUUUUUUUUUUUUUUUUUGAGACGGAGUCUUGCUCCGUCGCCCAGGCUGAAGUGCAGUGGCGCAAUCUCAGUUCACCGCAAGCUCCUCCUCCUGGGUUCACGCCAUUCUCCUGCCUCAGCCUCCAGAGUACCUGAGACUACAGGCGUGUGCCACCACGCCGGGCUAAUUUUUUUAAAGUAUUUUUAGUAGAGAUGGGGUUUCACCGUGUUAGCCAGGAUGGUCUCGAUCUGCUGACCUCGUGAUCCGCCUGCCUCGGCCUCUCAUGUCUUCGUAAUUUUCCAUGGAAAAAAACUUAAAUCUUUGGAAGGAAUAGAGUACAUUAUUGCAUUUUACAAAGAAAAGGAUAACUUUUAUAGAAUAAUGACCUUGUAUUCUUUUAGGAUUUUACAGCUACUUUUUCACAACUAUAGGCAUAGAAAAUGACAUCAGGGGCCGGGCGCGGUGGCUCACGCCUGUAAUCCCAACACUUUGGGAGGCCCAGGCGGCGGAUCACGAGGUCGAGAUUGAGACCAUCCUGGCCAACAUGAUGAAACCGCGUCUCUGCUAAAAAUACAAAAAUUAGCUGGGCGUGGUGUCGGGCGCCUGUAGUCCCAGCUACUCGGGAGGCUGAGGCAGGAGAAUUGCUUGAACCUGGGAGGCGGAGCUUGCAGUGAGCCCAGAUCGUACCACUGCACUCCAGCCUGGGCGACAGAGCAAGACUGUCUCAGAAAAAAAAAAAAAAAAAAAAAAAAGAAAUGACAUCAGGUCAUGGUGUUUGCUAUUGAUCGACACUUAAAUAGCCUUUGAAUUUUGUUUCAAAGGAGAUGCCAGAAUUGCAAAUUUUCUCUGCUGAUUUGUGUCCUACUGAUUCUGGCUCGCUUUCCCCCUACACUACUAGGGCUACUCUCACUUUCACACCUAGCAAAACUUCACCUUUCAAAGAAUUUAGGCAGAAUAGUCCUAAUUUAGUUAAUAAGCUUUCAUUUUAAAUCUUAGGGAAGCAGUGUUAGUUUCAGUUAUUCUAUAGGAACAGAAAUUGGAGCUGCCACAGCCUUUUGAACCAGAGCCCGGCAGACCCUCAGCUUCAGCCCUGCUCAGUGUUUUGUGUCUAUGAAAGUCUUUUUAAUUUUCUCAUUACACAUUUUAUAUAUCAUGCUAUGUAUUUAGAACAGAGGGGUUGUGUAAGAUUAUGACUCUAUGUUCUUUAUCUUGUCUUUGUAUUAAUUUGAAGUUGUGUUUUUUCUUUAUUUGUAGCCAACUAAUUAAAAUACCAACAUAUUUAUUUUUAUUCAUUUUUAUGUGACAAACUUUUAAACUGAAGACUGCAUCAAUAAAAUUGCAUGCCAUUAAAUAUGA